CUUUCCGAGGCCUCUGGCCAUCUGAGACAGCCAUAUCCAGAAGGAAGAGGAGCCGCGUUCCGUGGCUCACACCUGUAACCCCACCAGUUUGGGAGGCCGAGGCGGGCGGAUCACCUGAGGCUGAGGCCGGGGGUUUGAGACCAGCCUGACCAAUAUGGAGAAACCCCGUCUCUACUAAAAAUACAAAAUUAGCCGGGAGUGGUGGCGCAUGCCUGUAAUUCCAGCUACUCGGGAGGCUGAGGCAGGAGAGUCGCUUGAACCCGGGAGGCGGAGGUUGCGGUGAGCCGAGAUCGCGCCAUUGCACUCUAGCCUGGGCAACAAGAGGGAAAACUCCGUCUAAAAAGAAUAAGAGGGUUACAAGUAGCCUGAAUUUUCCUCUCUUCAAAUAGGGACUUCUCAAAGAAGGUGAAUCUAUAAUAGUGGUGUAGAUUCAGAUAUAAGGACACGUAUUUGGCGUAAAGGAGAGGCAAAGUUAGAGGAACCAGAAAGAAUGCUACACAAAAGAUGGCCGGCUUCUCGCGUGAAGGAAGAUUCGGAUACGGGGGCCUGAUGGAUUUAGUUGUAGGCGGUUUGCCUGCAGCGAGUAAAUUAUUCAAACGUUCGGACUUCACAAGACUAAACUUACUGGGGAUAAAAAUUGAGAUUUGGCCGGGCGCGAUGGCUCACGCCUGUAAUCCCUACACUUUGGGAGGCCGAGGCGGGUGGAUGAUCUGAGAUCAGGAGUUCGAGACCAGCCUGGCCGAAAUGGCGAAACCCCGUCUCUAUUAAAAAUACAAAAAUUAGCCGGGAGUGGUAGCGUCCGCCUGUAAUCCCAGCUACUCAGGAGGCUGAAGCAGGAGAAUCGGUGGAACCUGAGAGGCAGAGGCUGUAGUGAGCCGAGAUCGCGCCACUGCACUCCAGCCUGGGCGACAGAGCAAGACUCCGUCUAAAAAAAAAAAGAAAAAAAAAAAUUGAGAUUUGGUCCCAUGCAGUAAGAGGGAAUGGAGAACAGGAGCCACCCAACUUUGGACAUUAAAGUUGGAGCAGGCAAAGAUGAGGCCAGCUGUGUCGCGAAGCCUGGGACAUGGGCAGCUCUUGAGUACACCGGGUUCGAGGCCAGGGGAAACCCUCAAGCUCUGAAGAGACUGAGGGACUCGGCCAAUGCCAAUGAUGUGGAAACAGUGCAGCAGCUGCUGGAAGAUGGCGCGGAUCCCUGUGCAGCUGAUGACAAGGGCCGCACAGCUCUACACUUUGCCUCAUGCAAUGGCAAUGACCAGAUUGGCCAAGAGGCCCUCCCCAAAUCCUCAGUUCCUGGCCCUCAGGGCUUUGCCCAUGAACUCUGCUGCUCCUGGACCAUGGUGCUGAUCCUAACCAGCGAGAUGGGCUGGGGAACACGCCACUGCACCUGGCGGCCUGCACCAACCACGUUCCUGUCAUCACCACACUGCUACGAGGAGGUAUGUGGUUUCUUCCCCUCUCUGUCCUCUUUCUCCCCCUCACCCCCAGAAUGCUCACCUCAGCUGGUACCUGCAGGGGCCCGUGUAGAUGCCCUGGACCGAGCUGGUCGCACACCCCUGCACCUGGCCAAGUCAAAGCUGAAUAUCCUGCAGGAGGGCCAUGCCCAGUGCCUAGAGGCUGUGCGUCUGGAGGUGAAGCAGAUCAUCCAUAUGCUGAGGGAGUAUCUGGAGCGCCUAGGGCAACAUGAGCAGCGAGAACGCCUGGAUGACCUCUGCACCCGCCUGCAGAUGACCAGUACCAAAGAGCAGGUGGAUGAAGUGACUGACCUCCUGGCCAGCUUCACCUCCCUCAGUCUGCAGAUGCAGAGCAUGGAGAAGAGGUAGCAAGAGAGGCUCCCUGCCUUCCUGCCACUGCCCCACCCUGCCCCACUGCUGUCUCAGUACCAAGAAAAAGCCCAACAUCUGGGACUUGGAGCUGCACUUGUCUGGUGAGGACCUUGCCCUCACCCGCAGAUGCCGUGGGGCAGAGAUGCUCUCUCUCCACGGCCUCAGAGCCACUCCCAGCCACAGUUUCCAGCAUCUCUGUGGACAGGGACCACAGCUCCCAGCUUCUUCCAGUUCUCGCAGCACCAGACCAGCCUCUGCAGCUGCACUUCAGCUCCGCAGACCUGCGCUAUCUCAGCAGACCUCACUUGCCCCAUGGCCUUCAUGGCGCGCUCCAGGCCUCAGACCCUUCUCUGUGUUCCGUCCUGGCCAUGGGCUUGUUGCAGUCAGCAGGUGUGGGCUUAGGCGGGCACCCUGUGGCCAGGGGUACUGCGUGAGGCCCUCAGUUGGUCCUGUGCCUCUCACCAGCACUUAGACAGACACGUCACCAGACUUUCAAGGAGAUACUGCAGUGAGUUUCUCUGGUUGGAAGGGGAGGGUUGGUGAGUCCCAGACCUUAAAAAUACAAGGUUAAGAGGGACCCCAAAGCAAAAAAUUCCAACCCUUUUCCUCCCAGUCAUUGAAACACCAAAACUAUUAUACCGGAGGGUGUAAUAGUUUUGCUGCCCAGUUGUGGUAGGCCAGUAGUGGCCUCCCAAGAUGCCCAUGUCCUAAUCCCAGGAACCUGUCAAAAUUACCUUGUAUGGCCAAAGGGGCUUUGCAGAUGUAAUGAAGUUAAGGAUCUUUCGCCAGGAAGAUUAUCCCAGCUUGUUCAGGAGGGCUUGAUGUCCUCACCCGGGUCUGUAUAACAGAAGAGCAGGUGACGGGAGAGGAGGUUGGAGGUGUAGCGAUGGAGCAGGAAACUGGAGUUGAGGAGGGCAGCUCAAGCCACAGAGUCCAGGCCACCUCAGAGCCAGGAAAUGCAUCCUCCCACAGAGCCCUGGAAGGCCCCAGCCCUGCUCCCACCUGGACUGGCUCAGUGAGGCUAAUUUUAUAAUUCUGGCUGAUUUUAGAACUCUAAGGGAAUAAAUUUGUGUUGUUUUAAGUCA